CGCGCGCGACCCUCCCAGAGAGGGUCCCUGACUCUGGGAUCUGGCUUGGAUCCGGUAGUGAGGGGCUGACGGUGGGCUCCUGGGGAAGUCUCUGCCCCUAGACCCUGCUGAGGCUUCCAAGAGGCCUUCUCAGGCCUCGCCUCCACCCCCUGCCCGCUUAGCAGGGCCUCAGUUUCCCUGUGUGCUGGGGACCCGGGCCGGGGCUUGCUGAAGUGGCCGGUGCAGCUGGGACGCUUCCCGGCGGGGGCGCCUUCGGUGAACUGUGCCAGUGUUGUGGGGGUCCAUGCGUAGGGAUGGGGCCCAGCUUGGGGAGCCUGGCGUAAACUCUCCCAACCCCAACCCACAAACAAAGCAGAUGGGGUCACGGUGAGCCAGCCGGGGUAGGGCCUCCUGGAGAUGGUGAUCUUUGACAUACACCUUUGGGGGAAAGAGCAUUCCAGACAGGAAGGCGCAGAUGAAAGCCUGGCGGUGGGGUUGGGGGAGAAGGUGGGGCAGAAUGCCCCCUCUGGAGGAGGGAGGUUAGUGCCAUGCCCAGACCAGGAGAGACCCCAGCUGGCUGCCUCUGAGCCUUUUCCAGGGAGCCAGGUGUCCUGAGGGGGCAGAACAAUGAUACUGGCUGGGGACUCCUGGGCCACUCCACCUGCCAAAGCCCCUGUGUUCUCUUCCUGUACCGGGACGCCUGGACCCACACAGGCCAAGGGUCUGGGGCUUGUCCCAACCCACAUACCUCACAGCUUCCACACCCUCAAGAGACCCCCGAUACUGCUGAAUCCCUAAAAAGCCCCACCCCAGCUAUCAGCAGACAGGGCAGGAUCCACAGCUGGCCCAGUGACACAGAACAAAACCAGCCCCCUCUGCAGGCUCCUCUGUGGUUUUCUGAGCAGCGCAGGGGUCUAAGCCCAACCAGGAGGGGGCGGAGGCAUAGGGACCCCUCUUCCAAGGACCCCUUGAGGCUAAGCCAGCUCCGCCCCAGGGCACCUGUACACUUGCUACCUCUGAGGCUAGGGCCAGGACCAGAGGAGCCCAACAGCUGCCCAGGGAGAGGGCGAGUGAGCAGACUGUUCUGUCGGGGGACCUGGGGCCCAAGUCAGGGGAGCCCUGGGGGACCCUUCCCAGAUCUGCCUGUGGACAUCUCUACUGCCUCCCCACAAGCCUGGGCAGGCCAGCUCUGCACCCCAGCCCUCUCCACUUCCUGGACCUCCCUAAGCUGAGGACCUAGACAUCCCCACUGCAGCCCCAGGGGGUUCCACGCCCUGGGAUCUGAGCAUCUGUAGGGAUGCUUCUCUUCACCCCAAUUCUGCCCCUCCUGGUCCUCCUACCCAAGGACACUCAAUCCAGGGCCACCCUCUGCUCCAGGGCCAUGCCUGGGCGUCAGCAUCCAUGCCUGUUCCUCAGUCCAGACUUUGAGAGCUCAAAUCCUUCAGGAGAGACUACAGUCCCUGGCACUAACCCUGAGUUCUCAGUUCUGAUGGUGAGAAGCUGACCAGUGAGACCGACGGCCGGGGGGUCCACGCUGCGCCAUCCACACAGAGGGCUGAGGACUCCAGUGAGAGCCGUGAAGAGGAGCAAGCGCCCGAAGGUCGGGACCUAGACAUGCUGUUUCCUGGGGGGGCUGGGAGGCUGCCACUGAACUUCACCCAUCAGACACCCCCAUGGCGGGAGGAGUACAAGGGGCAGGUGAACCUGCACGUGUUUGAGGACUGGUGUGGGGGCGCCGUGGGCCACCUGAGGAGGAACCUGCACUUCCCGCUGUUCCCUCAUACGCGCACCACCGUGAAGAAGUUGGCCGUGUCCCCCAAGUGGAAGAACUAUGGACUCCGUAUUUUUGGUUUCAUCCACCCGGCGAGGGACGGAGACGUCCAGUUUUCUGUGGCCUCAGACGACAACUCGGAGUUCUGGCUGAGUCUGGACGAGAGCCCUGCUGCUGCCCAGCUUGUGGCCUUUGUGGGCAAGACUGGCUCCGAGUGGACAGCGCCUGGAGAAUUCACCAAGUUCAGCUCCCAGGUGUCCAAGCCCAGGCGGCUCAUGGCCUCCCGGAGGUACUACUUUGAGUUGCUGCACAAGCAGGACGACCGCGGCUCGGACCACGUGGAAGUGGGCUGGCGAGCUUUCCUGCCCGGCCUGAAGUUCGAGGUCAUCAGCUCUGCUCACAUCUCCCUGUACACAGAUGAGUCAGCCUUGAAGAUGGACCACGUGGCGCACGUCCCCCAGUCUCCAGCCAGCCACGUGGGGGGGCGUCCGCCGCAGGAGGAGACCAGCGCAGACAUGCUGCGGCCAGAUCCCAGGGAUACCUUUUUCCUCACUCCACGCAUGGAAUCUUCGAGCCUGGAGAACGUGCUGGAGCCCUGCGCCUACGCCCCCACCUACGUGGUCAAGGACUUCCCGAUCGCCAGAUACCAGGGCCUGCAAUUUGUGUACCUGUCCUUCGUUUAUCCCAACGACUACACUCGCCUCACCCACAUGGAGACGGACAACAAGUGCUUCUACCGCGAGUCUCCGCUGUAUCUGGAGAGGUUUGGGUUCUAUAAAUACAUGAAGAUGGACAAGGAGGAGGGGGAUGAGGAUGAAGAAGACGAGGUGCAGCGCCGAGCCUUCCUCUUCCUCAACCCGGACGACUUCCUGGACGACGAGGACGAGGGGGAGCUGCUCGACAGCCUGGAGCCCACCGAGGCGGCCCCGCCCAGGAGCGGCCCCCAGUCCCCCGCCCCAGCAGCCCCCGCCCAGCCCGGAGCCACCCUCGCCCCGCCGACCCCUCCCCGCCCCCGGGACGGGGGGACCCCCAGGCACUCCCGGGCCCUGAGCUGGGCCGCCAGGGCCGCCCGCCCUUUGCCGCUCUUCUUGGGCCGAGCUCCGCCCCCGCGCCCUGCAGUGGAGCAGCCGCCCCCAAAGGUGUACGUGACCAGGGUGCGGCCGGGACAGCGGGCAUCCCCCCGGGCCCCAGCGCCGCGUGCGCCCUGGCCGCCCUUCCCUGGCGUCUUCCUGCACCCCAGGCCUCUGCCCAGAGUGCAGCUGCGGGCGCCCCCACGCCCACCCCGGCCCCACGGCCGCAGGACCGGCGGCCCCCAGGCCACACAGCCGAGGCCCCCAGCCCGGGCGCAGGCCACCCAAGGGGGCCGGGAGGGCCAGGCGCGCACGCUGGGACCUGCGGCGCCCACAGUGGACUCAAACUUGUCCUCCGAAGCGCGGCCCGUGACCUCCUUCCUGAGCUUGUCCCAGGUGUCCGGGCCGCAGCUGCCCGGGGAGGGCGAAGAGGAGGAGGAAGGGGAGGACGAUGGGGCCCCGGGCGACGAGGCCGCGUCGGAGGACAGCGAGGAGGCCGCGGGCCCGGCGCUCGGACGCUGGCGUGAGGACGCCAUCGACUGGCAGCGCACGUUCAGCGUGGGCGCCGUGGACUUCGAGCUGCUGCGCUCGGACUGGAACGACCUGCGAUGCAACGUUUCGGGGAACCUGCAGCUGCCGGAGGCGGAGGCCGUGGACGUGACCGCUCAGUACAUGGAGCGGCUGAACGCGCGCCACGGCGGGCGCUUCGCGCUUCUGCGCAUCGUGAACGUGGAGAAGCGCCGGGACUCGGCGCGAGGGAGUCGCUUCCUGCUGGAGCUGGAGCUGCAGGAGCGCGGGGGCGGCCGCCUGCGACUGUCCGAGUACGUCUUCCUGCGGCUGCCGGGAGCCCGCGUAGGGGAUGCAGACGGAGAAAGUCCCGAACCCGCUCCCGCCGCCUCCGUGCGCCCCGACGGCCGCCCCGAGCUCUGCCGGCCACUGCGCCUGGCCUGGCGCCAGGACGUGAUGGUUCACUUCAUCGUGCCAGUGAAAAACCAGGCACGGUGGGUGGCACAGUUCCUGGCGGACAUGGCUGCGCUGCACGCGCGCACCGGGGACUCGCGUUUCAGCGUCGUCCUGGUGGAUUUCGAGAGCGAGGAUAUGGACGUGGAGCGGGCCCUGCGCGCCGCGCGCCUGCCCCGGUACCAGUACCUGAGACGAACCGGGAACUUCGAGCGCUCCGCCGGGCUGCAGGCGGGAGUGGACGCGGUAGAGGACGCCAGCAGCAUCGUGUUCCUCUGCGACCUGCACAUCCACUUCCCACCCAACAUCCUGGACGGCAUCCGCAAGCACUGCGUGGAGGGCAGGCUGGCCUUCGCGCCCGUGGUCAUGCGCCUGAGCUGCGGGAGCUCGCCCCGGGACCCCCACGGUUACUGGGAGGUGAACGGCUUUGGCCUUUUUGGGAUCUACAAGUCGGACUUUGACCGGGUUGGAGGAAUGAACACGGAGGAGUUCCGAGACCAGUGGGGGGGUGAAGACUGGGAGCUCCUGGACAGGGUCCUGCAGGCAGGGCUGGAGGUGGAGCGGCUCCGACUGCGGAAUUUCUAUCACCACUACCACUCCAAGAGGGGCAUGUGGAGCGUCCGCAGCAGGAAGGGCUCUCGCACGGGGGCGUCUUGAGGACGGGCAGCCCCUCCCAGCCCCGGUGGGAGUCCCGAGGCAGCUGCUGGGGGCUGGGCUUUGAGCUCGGUCCCGAGAGACCCGGCAGGGCUGGUCAGAGGGGCACAGCCACCGCCUGUGCCUGCCCCUCUCUGGCCCACUGGGCGUCGUGCCCCUCCCCGGAGAGGCAGCCUUCACGGCGGGUCAGGGCCUGGCCUUGGUCCCCACUCUGCGAUGAUUUCUGUGAAAUUUUGCUGUAGCGAUGACAUUGUUUUCAGAAUUUCCAAGAGUUCUGUCUGUUCUGUUUUUUAUUCAGAAUGAAAUGAAAUAUUUUUUUUAGUUCUGA